GUCUUUCAACUCCUCCCAGCUGGGACACUGCACCGGGAGGCAGCACGGAUUCCUGUGUCAUCAAGAUUCGCUCUGCCUCGAGUCUCCAGGAGCUUCCAGUGGCUUGGUUACCCCCGACUCUUCGUCCAUGCCUCUUAGAGCCCCUUUCCCAGCCUCACUGGGUGUCCCUUAAUAGUCUUGGGACCUUAAGGAGCAAGUCAGCCCCUGCGGAACCUCCCAGUGAAGAGAAAGAGCUGGCUGUGCGGUGGAACUUGGAAGAGACGACGUCUGGGAGCUUUUGCUGAGCCCAGGGGGAGAGGCGUCCCUCUGGCUGCUGCUCCAGCUCUGGCAGACACGCCAAGCUUUGAGAAAGCUCCCAGUGAGGAACUGGUCUUCUGGAGACUCUGUGUGGCAUAGAGUGAUUCAACCACCUUAAGAAGACCUCUGGCUUUCCUGGAACACAGAUGUCGAGACAUCUCCCAUGGAUUUGUGAUCAGCGUUGCAGCUCUCCCAGCAGCCCUGGACGGUGGUGAGUCCCCUCAGCUGGCCAGGACAGUACUCUGCUCUCACCUCUCUGCUUCUUGGGCUCCAUCCCAGCUCCCCAUCAACUGAUCUUCUUGCAAACCCACAGGGCUCCAGGACACCCUCCUUCUGGAGCCCAUGCUGCCUACAGCACUUCACUCCCCACCAGUGAUGACAACAGUUGCUGUUCUUUGUCCACUUUAUUUACUUGUUUAUCUUUAAUGACAAAAGUUUUUUUUUUGUUGUUUUUUUUUUUUUUUUUGAAACGGAGUCUCACUCUUCACUCAGGCUGCAGUGCAGUGGCGCAAUCUCAGCUCACUGCCACCUCUGCCUCCCAGGUUCACGCCAUUCUCCUGCCUCAGCCUCCCGAGUAGCUGGGACUACAGGCGCCCACCAUCACGCCUGGCUAAUUUUUUGUAUUUUUAGUAGAGAUGGGGUCUCACUGUGUUAGCCAGGAUGGUCUCGAUCUCCUGACCUCGUGAUCCGCCCGCCUCGGCCUCCCAUAAUGCUGGGAUUACAGGCGUGAGCCACCGCGCCUGGCUGACAAAAGUUUUAUACCUGCCUGUUAAAAAAAUUAUAUAAUACAGAAGCACACCUUGUAAAAGGUGCAAUCCUCAGUUAUGGGCAUGACUGCGUGUUCCCUUCCCCCAUCUUCAUUAUAAUAACCCCCCAAUCCCCCCAGAUCCUGUGAGCCAGGUACCGGAAUUAUCCCUCUUUCACACACGGGUAAAGUGAUCCGUCACAGAGAGAUUUAAGUGAUCUUCAUAAGCAAGAUCAUAGGCUAGGAAGUGGCAGAGCCAGGAUUCAACCUCGGCGAGCCUGGUGGUGCUCUGACAUCCACCGAAGCCCCCAUCAAGCCCUUUUAGCUCCACAACCUAAAAGGGUCUCUCUAAGAGGUAUCCUGAAGCAAAAGACAGGAGUUCUCUUUGAAACAUAGUAUUUCUCUCUACAGAUAGAUAGCCUGUAGGUAUGUAAGUAGGUGGGUGGGUGGGUAGGUAGACAGUUUGAUGAUAUCCCACAUUAUUCUGCAACUGGACUUCUGCUGUGAGCACAGACUAUAUUCUGGCCUAUGUCUUGACUCCGUAUUCCUGGGAAAGUGCUCGACUGAGACCUUGGGAGUCUUGGGAAGUCCAAUGGGUAGGGUAGCCGAAUCUGAGGGCUGAUCCCUGAGGGCACUGGGCAGUAAUUGGGGCAUGGGAUGGGCAUGAGGGCCCGGGUCCCUAAAGUUGCCCACUCCACCCGAAGGCCCCCAGCCGCCCGCAUGUGGCUGCCACGGUUCUCCAGCAAGACAGUGACAGUGCUCCUCCUGGCACAGACCACCUGCCUCCUGCUCUUCAUCAUCUCCCGGCCAGGGCCCUCAUCCCCAGCCGGCGGCGAGGAUCGUGUGCACGUGCUGGUGCUGUCCUCGUGGCGCUCGGGCUCAUCCUUCUUGGGCCAGCUCUUCAGCCAGCACCCCGACGUCUUCUACCUGAUGGAGCCCGCGUGGCAUGUGUGGACCACCCUGUCGCAGGGCAGCGCGGCAACGCUGCACAUGGCCGUGCGCGACCUGAUGCGCUCUAUCUUUUUGUGCGACAUGGACGUGUUUGAUGCCUACAUGCCACAGAGCCGAAACCUGUCCGCCUUUUUCAACUGGGCAACGAGCCGCGCGCUGUGCUCGCCGCCCGCCUGCAGCGCCUUUCCCCGAGGCACCAUCAGCAAGCAGGACGUAUGCAAGACACUGUGCACGCGGCAGCCAUUCAGCCUGGCCCGGGAGGCCUGCCGCUCCUACAGCCACGUGGUGCUCAAGGAGGUGCGCUUCUUCAACCUGCAGGUGCUCUACCCGCUGCUCAGCGACCCCGCGCUCAACCUGCGCAUCGUGCACCUGGUGCGCGACCCGCGGGCCGUGCUGCGCUCCCGGGAGGCGGCGGGCCCGAUACUGGCACGCGACAACGGCAUCGUGCUGGGCACCAACGGCAAGUGGGUGGAGGCCGACCCUCACCUGCGCCUGAUUCGCGAGGUGUGCCGCAGCCACGUGCGCAUCGCCGAGGCCGCCACACUCAAGCCGCCACCCUUCCUGCGCGGCCGCUACCGCCUGGUGCGCUUCGAGGACCUGGCGCGGGAGCCGCUGGCAGAGAUCCGCGCACUCUACGCCUUCACCGGCCUGACCCUCACGCCACAGCUCGAGGCCUGGAUCCACAACAUCACCCACGGGUCGGGGAUCGGCAAGCCAAUCGAGGCCUUCCAUACUUCGUCUAGGAAUGCGCGCAACGUCUCCCAGGCCUGGCGCCACGCGUUGCCCUUCACUAAGAUCCUGCGCGUGCAGGAGGUGUGCGCCGGCGCGCUGCAGCUGCUGGGCUACCGGCCUGUGUACUCUGCGGACCAGCAGCGUGACCUCACCCUGGAUCUGGUGCUGCCACGAGGCCCAGACCACUUCAGCUGGGCAUCGCCUGACUGAGAACUCUGGGCCUUAGAGCAGGCCCCGAACUGUGGUCGCCAGGCCCAGGAGGCGACUGCAUGGUGGAGAGGGAGCUGGGGCGCAUGGGGAAGCAGGUCCCUACUAUCAACCGGGAGUUUGGGGUCCUCCCCUGAAGUAGGCAAGGACUGCACGUUUCUUUCUCUCCUGAUUCUCGGUUUUCCUUUGAGUCUUCUGGAGCUGCCUUCUCAUCAGGUGCACUCUUCAUGGAAAGCAACUCUUGCCCCUACCUCUUCUGGGCGCAGGGAGUAAGUUACUGCUAAAUUAAAUUAAAUGUGUGCCAGGCCGGGUGCGGUGGCUCAUGCCUGUAAUCCCAGCAUUUUGAGAGGCUGAGGCGGGUGGAUCACCUGAGGUCAGGAGUUCGAAACCAGCCUGGCCAACAUAGUGAAACCCCCUCUCUACUAAAAAUGCAAAAAUUAGUCCGGCGUGGUGGCACACUCCUGUAAUCCCAGCUACUUAGGAGGCUGAGGUGGGAGAAUCACUUGGACUCCAGAGGUGGAGGUUGCAGUAAGCUGAGAUCAUGCCACUGCACCCUAGCUUGGGUGGCAGAGCAAGACUCUAUCAAAAAAAUAAGUAAUAAAUUUGUUCAAAAGUCCUGCAA